CCAGUGAACCUCGCCCGAGAGCUCCAUUAAUAAAGCAGGUCGCCUCUGACCAUUAGUCACCUAAAUUCUGUGCGGUAGUUCUCAUUGGAUACCUGUCUUCCCAAGCCGGACAUUGGUGCCAAAACCCGGGAGGAGACCCCUCUCUGACCCAGGGUCGGGGAGCAUCUCCUCUCCCUACCUGCCAGGAACCAGACUCGGGCCAGCGCAUUCGGCCUUUGCUAUUGGAUGGGACAUUGGAAGUCUGAGUGCCCCAGCGUCGGAGCGUCCACAGUGCCUCUACGCUGUGAAAACUCCGAGACGACCGGUGGCGCCUUCCAAUUACUCAGCAUGGACGACGACUGAAGAGGCCCAGACUCGGGAACCCCCCUCACUCUUGCCGAGCCCAGGGUAACGCUCCAGGUAGCAGAUACCUUCACAGGCUGGAUUGAGGCCUUUCCCACUGCACGUGAGACAGGAGAAGUCGCAGUCUCUGUCCUGCUAGAACAUAUCAUCCCUCGCUUUGGACUUCCCCGAUCCCUGCAAUCAGACAACGGCCCCGCGUUCGUCUCAAAAAUCACUCAGCAAGUAUCCGAGUCGCUCCGCGUCACAUGGAAGCUCCAUAUCCCUUACCGCCCUCAAUCCUCUGGUAAAGUAGAAAGGGCUAACAGCCUCCUCAAAGAACACCUUACAAAACUUACUCUUGAAACAAAGCUGUCGUGGGUCACCCUCCUACCAUUGGCCCUGACCCGCCUCCGGGCAGCUCCCAGGGGCCCCACAGGGCUCAGCCCCUUCGAACUUCUCUACGGACGCCCCUUCCUACUUCCUGGUCUUCCCCCCACUGUUUCGCCCCCUCCCCUCGCGUCCUAUCUUCCUUAUCUGACCCUCCUUCGCGACCUUCUCCGCAAGCACGCGGACGCCUGCCUCCCCGAACCUACCCCCUCCUCCCCGGACGCCCCUGUUGUGCUCUCUCCAGGUGAUAGUGUCCUCCUUAAGGAACUACAGUCCAAGACCUUGACCCCGCGGUGGUCAGGCCCUUACACCGUGAUCCUCACCACUCCGAGGGCCACUAAGUUACUAGGUCUACCAUCCUGGUAUCAUUUGUCACAGUUGAAGAAAGCACCGACUCAGCACGACUGGUCCUCAAAACUCACCCCAACCCGGCUUCGUAUCACCCAUGGCCAGACCUUCCCCACUAUGCCUCCUACUCCUCCUGACCCUCCUAACCCCCAUAGUGCCCAGUAACUCCCUCCUAACUGAACCCCCGUUCCGAUGGAGGUUCUACCUGCAUGAGACUUGGACCCAAGGCAACCGGCUCUCCACUGUCACACUGGCAACGGUGGACUGCCAACCUCACGGUUGUCAGGCCCAAGUAACUUUUAACUUCACUUCCUUUAAAAGUGUUCUGCGGGGCUGGUCCAAUCCCACCAUCUGCUUUGUCUAUGAUCAAACACACAGCAACUGCCGCGACUAUUGGGUGGACACAAACGGAGGAUGCCCCUAUGCCUAUUGUCGUAUGCAUGUGACCCAGCUCCAUACCGCCAAGAAACUCCAACACACCUAUCGCCUGACAUCUGAUGGAAGGACAACUUACUUCCUGACCAUCCCAGACCCAUGGGAUUCUCGGUGGGUCAGUGGAGUCACUGGUCGACUGUACCGGUGGCCCACCGACUCCUACCCAGUUGGCAAACUCCGGAUAUUCCUGACUUAUAUACGAGUUAUCCCCCAGGUUUUGUCUAAUUUAAAGGACCAAGCAGACAACAUUAAGCAUCAGGAAGAGGUCAUCAAUACUUUGGUGCAGUCCCAUCCGAAGGCUGACAUGGUCACCUAUGAUGACAAGGCUGAGGCAGGACCGUUUUCAUGGAUAACCCUAGUCCGCCACGGGGCUCGCCUUGUUAAUAUGGCAGGCCUAGUUAAUCUCUCCCACUGUUUCCUUUGCACCGCCCUCAGCCAACCACCACUAGUAGCUGUACCCCUACCCCAGGCUUUUAACACCUCUGGUAACCACACUGCCCACCCUUCCGGCGUCUUCUCUGAGCAGGUCCCUCUUUUCCGAGACCCCCUCCAGCCCCAGUUCCCCUUCUGCUACACCACUCCUAACUCAUCCUGGUGCAACCAGACCUAUUCUGGCUCCCUAUCUAACCUCUCUGCACCGGCAGGUGGCUACUUCUGGUGUAACUUCACCCUUACAAAACAUCUUAAUAUUUCCUCUAACAAUACCCUUUCUAGAAACUUAUGCCUCCCCAUCUCUCUGGUGCCUCGACUCACUCUGUACAGCGAGGCUGAACUCUCUUCCCUUGUCAACCCGCCUAUGCGUCAGAAGCGGGCCGUUUUCCCACCGCUGGUAAUAGGUGUCUCCUUGACCUCCUCACUUGUUGCCUCCGGGCUGGGCACAGGUGCUAUUGUACAUUUCAUAAGCUCUUCCCAAGAUCUCUCUAUUAAGCUCCAGAUGGCCAUCGAAGCCUCAGCCGAAUCCUUAGCCUCUCUACAGAGACAGAUUACGUCUGUGGCCAAGGUGGCCAUGCAGAACCGGAGAGCCCUAGAUCUCCUCACAGCCGACAAAGGCGGAACCUGCAUGUUUCUCGGGGAAGAGUGCUGUUAUUACAUCAAUGAAUCAGGCUUAGUAGAAACCAGCCUCCUCACCCUUGAUAAAAUCCGGGACGGUCUCCAUCGACCCUCCUCAACUCCCAACUAUGGAGGAGGGUGGUGGCAAUCCCCUUUAACCACUUGGAUUAUCCCUUUCAUAAGCCCCAUCCUAAUCAUUUGCCUUUUACUUCUCAUAGCCCCCUGUGUCCUCAAGUUCAUCAAAAACCGCAUCAGCGAAGUCUCCCGGGUGACGGUCAACCAAAUGUUACUACACCCUUACUCCCGUCUUCCGACCUCCGAAGACCACUAUGACGACGCCCUCACUCAGCAGGAAGCAGCCAGAUGAUUACGUCGCCCCUUUUUCUUACAGUAUGAGGUCGGAAUGUUAGGCAGGUCACCCAAGAUGGCUGUUCCCCCAGGACCCAAGAUGGCGGCACGAACCCCUUCUUCCCCGCCCCCCCCACCGCUUGGAGUCUCCCACCAGAUUUUCCCGCCCGACGGGCACUUUCCGAUGACAGCAGCCCCGAGAAGUCGAAACCUAUCCCAGAAAACCGAAACUUACUAAGCCCCUCCCCACACGCUCUAUAAAAACCCUCUACUGCCCCAGUCGGGUGCGACUUCCCUGGCCCUCCUUGUUAGGACCAGUGAACCUCGCCCGAGAGCUCCAUUAAUAAAGCAGGUCGCCUCUGACCAUUAGUUACCUAAAUUCU